AACUUAGCGCCCGGGGUCUCUGCCAGGCUCACGGGACAGCUGCACCUCUCAGCGUCUCCAGCUCCAGGACGCGGUCGUCCCAACUCCUUCCGAGUGGAAAGAGUGUAAAACUUUUGUCCGUGCGCGGGUGGAGCUCAGUAGGACCACGGCGCGUCCUGCCCCGGCUUCCCCAGCCUCCCAGCAGGGUUAGCUGCGGUCAGCGCACUUUCCACUUGGGACUCCCGGCCAGAAAUUUCUCGGGAAUGGAGCGGUCACAGUGUGGCAGCAGAGACCGAGGCGUUAGCGGCCGACCUCACUUGGCCCCUGGGCUAGUGGUGGCUGCCCCUCCGCCCCCGUCCCCGGCGUUGCCGGUACCAUCGGGGAUGCAGGUUCCCCCAGCGUUCCUGCGGCCGCCCAGCCUCUUUCUGCGAGCAGCGGCCGCGGCCGCCGCCGCCGCUGCCGCCACCUCGGGAAGCGGAGGCUGCCCGCCGGCUCCCGGGCUGGAGAGCGGGGUAGGCGCGGUGGGCUGCGGCUACCCGCGGACGCCCAAGUGCGCCCGCUGUCGUAACCAUGGUGUGGUGUCAGCGCUCAAGGGCCACAAGCGCUUCUGCCGCUGGCGGGACUGCGCGUGUGCCAAGUGCACCCUGAUCGCCGAGCGCCAGCGCGUCAUGGCCGCCCAGGUGGCGCUGCGCAGGCAGCAGGCGCAGGAGGAGAGCGAAGCCCGGGGGCUACAGAGGCUCCUGUGCUCGGGGCUCUCCUGGCCCCCCGGUGGUCGGGCAUCCGGGGGCGGCGGCAGAGCCGAGAAUCCACAGUCCACGGGCGGCCCUGCGGCGGGGGCUGCGCUGGGACUGGGUGCCUUGAGACAGGCCAGUGGUUCCGCGACCCCCGCUUUCGAAGUUUUCCAGCAAGAUUAUCCUGAGGAAAAACAAGAACAAAAAGAGAGUAAAUGUGAGUCAUGCCAGAAUGGACAAGAAGAACUGAUCUCCAAAUCCCAUCAGCUUUACCUAGGAUCAUCUUCUAGGUCUAAUGGUGUCAUUGGGAAACAAAGUAUCGGGUCAUCUAUUUCAGAAUACUCCAACAAGCCUGAUAGUAUCCUGUCUCCUCAUCCUGGAGAGCAAUCAGGAGGUGAAGAGAGUCCCAGGUCCUUAUCAUCCUCUGAUCUGGAAUCAGGAAAUGAAAGUGAAUGGGUCAAAGACUUGACUGCGACCAAGGCAAGCCUUCCGACAGUGUCCUCAAGACCAAGAGAUCCUCUUGAUAUCCUUACUAAGAUUUUCCCAAAUUACAGGCGCAGCCGGCUAGAAGGCAUUCUACGGUUCUGCAAAGGGGAUGUGGUCCAAGCCAUUGAACAGGUUUUAAAUGGCAAAGAACACAAGCCAGACAACAGGAACCUAGCAAACUCAGAAGAACUGGAAAACACAGCCUUUCAGAGAGCUUCAAGUUUUAGUCUUGCUGGAAUUGGUUUUGGAACUCUAGGUAAUAAAUCAGCUUUCUCUCCUCUUCAAACUACUUCUGCUUCUUAUGGAGGUGAUUCAAGUCUCUACGGCGUAAAUCCUAGAGUAGGUAUCAGUCCAUUAAGGCUGGCAUAUUCUUCUGCAGGAAGAGGGUUAUCUGGUUUUAUGUCACCCUACCUAACACCUGGGUUAGUACCAACCUUACCUUUUCGGCCAGCUUUGGAUUAUGCCUUUUCAGGGAUGAUUAGAGAUUCUUCCUACCUUUCCAGUAAAGACUCAAUAACUUGUGGCAGACUGUACUUCAGACCAAAUCAGGACAAUCCGUAAUGUAUAUGCCCAUUCUCUCUUUCUGGAGUUUUUCCAGCAUACAAUACAUGCACGUGCACACACAUACACACACAUCCAUUAAUAUACUUCAGUAAGUAUGUGAGUGGAUUAUGAGGUCUUAAAAUGCUGGGUUUUUUUUUUUUCAAGCAAUAUAAUAGGUCUUAGAUCUGAAAACUCUUCAUUAGGAUUUAUCAAGUGAAAGAAGUAAAUCUGAACAUUAUAUGUGCCUUGAAUAAAGCUAUUUCAGGAAAUAUUUAAUGAAUUUUCUCCCUAAAUUAUCAUUUGUAAACAUUUUUAUUUUAAAACUAGUUUUUAUUUUAUUGAAAAGUGGAAUUUUUAGUGAUAAAAUACAUUUGUAAGUGUAAAGCAAUACAGCAUAAUAGAAUAGAAUAUAAACCGAAAGGAAGAACUGAACAAUUAAGGCAAUUCUAAAUAAUUACCAUUUCAAAACUGUUUCUUCUAUUCCUGGUUCAUAGGAAAGAAAAAAGUUAUUCAAAGUAUUUUUAAAGCAUUUGAUUUGCAGAUGGGUGAUUCGUAAUAAAUAAAACAUUUGAGCAUUUUGAAUUUAUAUUUCCUGAGUAUUUUAUUUUUCAAUCUUAGCUUCCAUGAGUGAAAACAAGUGCCAUUAAAAAACAUUUCUCUUUAAAGUUGACACUGUGUCUAUGAAGUAAAUUUUAGGAAAUAAGACUGCGCCAUCUCCUGGCCACUAUCGCCAAUUGCAACUGAGCUCUGUAGAGUAUAUGAAUUAGAAACAUUGAUUCCGGAGAAUAACCAUUUUUUUUUCAAAUAGUCAUUUUGGAUUAUACUACAUUAAAAUUUCCAUACUGUAAAGUGCACAUCUACUGUGGAUGAGAGUUGCAGUCUUUAAGUGUGCUUAUGUCUGUAUCUGGGGAAAUAUCCUUAAAAGUUUGGGACAAGAAUAUAUGGCAGCCAUUCUCAAAGGUAAGAAUAAUUUUAUUCAGAAAACUAAAAUAGCUGCUCAAAUAAAUAUUUAUUAACUGCAGAUAGUUGAUGCUUAAUGCACUGAGGAGAGAUAUAAGAUUUCCAAAGGGGAAAAACUGCCAUGAAGUUUCAGAGGUAUUCUUGCAAUUUUAAAAAUAAUUUUUGUCCUCCCUCUGGCGCAUUUGAAAACUAUUUAUUUCAGUCAGUGGAAAGUCCCUGAGGAAACUGCUUACAAAACAGUUUCUAGGACAUUUUCUUUGUAUGUCAUCAUUUUUCUUUUUUGAAGGACAGUAGCUUCAUUGUUAUUAUUAGGAAUAAAUGGAAGCCCACUGGUGGUAAAAGAUAGUUGAUGAAUUAGAGAUUGUUUAAACUAUUUAAGCAGCAUGACUCACUAAAGAUUUUUUAAAUUAUAUGUAUAUACGUAUGUGUGUAUGCAUCUAUAUGCACAUAUAUAAGUCUAUGUAGACAUACAUUAAACCCCUAUAGGUUAUAUUAUCAUGGAGGCGUUUUUCAUGAAGCCAGUAAGAAUGUAUUUCCAAGGAAUAUUUUGCCAGCAAAUGUGAUAUUAAAUUACUUCAGAGUAUCUGAUGCUGAUUUAGGAUGUAAAUGUGUUUAUUAGGUUAUGCAUUAAUUUUAAUGGUGUGAAUAUAAGAAAGCAGAUCUUGAAAAAUUUCGAUGUACUCAAUAUUCAUUUAUUAUAAAAAAGUUUUAUAUUCUAAGCCUAAACCGUAGUACAAUGUCUAGCAAGUAGUUGAAAUUCAAUUCAUAUAUACUGAGUAAGAAACUCUUAUAUAUAAUAGAUCUCUUUGAGACUCUGAUAAAACUGAAGAACUCUACAAAAUGGCGUACAGACACACAGUUUUGCAUACAAUUUCACUGGGUUCUUGAAUCUCCUAAAUGGUAUUCAGGUUAGAUUCCUUGGUGAUUCUUCAGUUGUUUCUAUUGCAUUAAUCCACUUAUUGAAUGCUAUUUUUCUGAAAAGUGCUAGAUCCUGUAGAGGAUACUGAAUGUAAAAUAUUGUGCUCUAAAGGAAGUUACAUUAUACAAUAGAGAUAUGGUUUAAAAAAAAAUCCUAGAGUUACUGCAUUAUGUAUGUGGUUUUAUAAUGAUGUGCUUGUAUCUGAGAAACUGAAUUGCUUUUGACCUUGGGAGAACAUCCAUUUUGGGCAGUAUUCGAAUUUAUAAAAUAGUUUUAUAAUCAUAAAACUUAAUUUAUAUAAUGCCUUACACAUUCCAUACUCUUUAUAAUAAUUUAAGGACUUAAUCUUAUCAAAUAGGUCAUUUGUCUAACAACUCAGUAGUAUAUGAGGAAAUUGGGGCUCAGCAGUAGGGUUUUUUCUCCCUAAGGUUAGUAAUAUGAGUCAUCUGCAGUGGAAUUACUGUGCUCACUUCAGCAAUUUCAGACUCCAAUGUCUGAGGAAGGAUUCAUGUCUGUUUUUUUCAUUCAUGGCCUUGAACAGUGUCUGAUAUAGGUUCUCAACCUAUACACUAGAUUUCCACUGACUGAAAAAAAAUAAAAGCAAGUAUUAGCUUAAUAAUUUCUUCAUUCAACACCUAUUUAAUAUUUUUAAUAAUCUAUUUGUGCCAUGCACUGUGUUAGACACAAGAGAUAAAGAAAUGAUUAAGAUACAAGACUUUGCCUCAAGUUGCUCACGGUCUAUAUUGUGUGUACAAAAACAACCAAUCAACCAAUGUUGGUAUUAUUUGACAGUGUUGGUACAUCAAUGAGUUCUUUGUAAUCUUGAUAUUUAUAUCCAUGGAUGCUGCUUGAAGCCUGAACUCCUAAGCCACUAAUUAGUGGUGGGAAGAAAGAGGGGGUAAAUGCUUUAAGAGCUAGCAUAUAACAAAAAUGAAUUGGGUUUAUUCUGUAUCAUAUAGAGGGCCUAAGAGGCAAACAUUUCAUAGAGUAUUCAGAAGAACAUAAGGAAUGACUUUUUUCACAGUUAACAGCUGUCCAAGAGUGUAGUGGCUGCCUCGUAUGAUAAAGCAUCUGGAACUCAUUGAAAAAUGCAUGUAGAAAAUACCAAUCAGAGCCUGAUUGAUGGGAUUUUUAAUUACUGCUUUAAUAUUGGGACUGAAUCAUUUUGUAGCUCAUUAGAAACAUGGAAAGUAUUUGUUAAAUAAAUAAGUCAUGGAAUUUCAAUUCUAAGGCCAUGAAAAUUAAAACACCCUACCAUUAUUUAUCAAUAAAACACAGUGCAGUUUUGCUCAUCAGAAUUUUGCCUAUGUGAUAGCCUCCUGAGAGUAGGCAGAAAAGAAAGACAUAGAACGCAGUGCGUGACUUACAAGGGAAUAAAACUGACAGAGGUUAGUGUAAGGUAUAUAGGCAUGAGUGGGGCUUAAAGAGGAUAUGGGAGAACACUGAAGACAAAUAUUAGUACAAUUCCUAUAAGGUAAAUACCAAUAUGUCUUUCUAGAAGAAGCAAUUGUUUUGGAAUUGAGGAAACCUAGAAUGGAUUUAUCUAUAUGACUUGGACAGGUUACUUAUACUCUUUGGACAUUUAUUUCUUCUCAGCAAAACAAGGGUAAUAAUAUUUAACUUGCAAGAUUCGUGGAGAUAAAAGCUUAAAUAAACGGCAGAGUACAGUAAUGCUUAUAUACGGGAUGCUAAAUAAAUAACUCUCACUGUUAUUACUUUGUAUUAAGAUAUUAUCUUUGCCCCCUCGUGGCAGUCUCUCAACAAAGAGUACUGUAAUUGCAUUUAAUCCACUUAGUGGAUGUGGAGCCCAAAGGGCAGCCAUCACUAGAGCAGCGUACAGGCUUAGUUCCAGACUUCGUGUUUGGUUGUUCAUUUCAUAGGCGAGCCACGUGUUUUGUAACAUAUUCUCGUAUAUGUUAUUUGGAUUAUUUUCAGGGCUUUCUGAAGAAAAUAAACAUCGAAAUCAUA